GGGAUCCGGGGACAGCGCGCACCCAGACCUCCUCAUUCCUUACGGGCAUGUAGAAAUUCCCCUUGACAGUCCUGUAGCCUGUCCUGCAGCCUCUGGCUCCCCCAACCCACCUCUACCCUCUCCGCCCUGGACACAUCAUCGCAUCUCCUGGAGCCCUCAGAACCCCCUCAUUCACUCAACAAAUCUCCUGCUAUGCCCACGGACCCACCAUUUCUCUUGGAUGCCCCCAAAUGCUUCCACUGCCCGGAAAUUCCUAGGAUCCCUCAUAUCCCCAUUCUCCUUGCACUAUCCAAAAUGCCCACAUCCAAAAUUCUUGCUCAUGUUUCCCCAAACGUCCUCAUACGUUUUCAGCCCCCACACCCCCCUCUCACUCCUGCCCCUGAUCCAUACCUAUCCCAGACCAGAGGCCUCUCCCCAUUUCCACUCAAUGCAGUCCCUCCUCAGUGGGCUAUCUGAUACAUCCUGAUAUCUUAAGGAGAAGAGAUGGUGAUAGGGAAAUUCAGCCCCUCCCCCAUCUUGCACCCUAGAGUUCUUCGUUUCAGUGCCCGCGCCGUGCCCCCGUCGGUGGCUCAAGCCCCAGUAUUUUCCCAGCAACCUAUCUUUAGUCUGUGCACACCUCCCUGAGCCUGCUUCUUCCUUCCAGAAAAUAAGCCAGACCAAGGGGAUGGGGUCCUUUUACCUGGAAGUUGUCCAAGGAUGCAGGGUGCAAGGGGCCCUGGGAAGUGUUUCUCCAGAGCAGGAAUGUGGGAUGUCCAGGGUCUGCAGAGUCCUGGCUUGUUGACUUGUCUACCUUGGGCUCAGAUAUCCUGAAAUUUUGGCUUACUGUUAACAUUUAUGUUAAAAUUAGGCCUUUCAGAGCUUGGGGAGCAGAAAAUCUAUCAAGCUUCCAAAUGCGAAAUUGAAGCAGCCUGUCUUGGAAGAUGAACAUGUCAAUUUUAGUGAAGUGAGCCCCAGGUGUAUCCCAGAGGGAUCCGGGUGACUUCUCUGCAGACUGUUUGCCAUGACAGCCCACCAAGGACGGGGGGAAUAAAGUGGGAACCCUUCCCCAUGCCCCUCCCACGGUCAGCUCCCCGAUGGCCUGGGUGAGGGCAGGCUGGCUGCUCUGACACCAUGGGGAGCUGCUGCAGCUGCCUGAACAGAGACAGCGUUCCAGACAACCACCCCACCAAGUUCAAGGUGACAAAUGUGGAUGAUGAGGGGGUGGAGCUGGGCUCUGGGGUGAUGGAGCUGACGCAGAGUGAGCUGGUGCUGCACCUGCAUCGGCGUGAGGCCGUCCGCUGGCCUUAUCUCUGCUUGCGGCGCUAUGGCUACGACUCCAACCUCUUCUCCUUUGAGAGUGGCCGCCGAUGUCAGACAGGCCAGGGAAUAUUUGCAUUUAAGUGUUCCCGGGCUGAGGAAAUCUUCAACCUCCUUCAGGAUCUGAUGCAGUGCAACAGCAUCAAUGUGAUGGAAGAGCCUGUCAUCAUCACCCGCAAUAGCCACCCCGCUGAGCUUGACCUCCCUCGAGCCCCCCAGCCACCCAAUGCUCUAGGCUACACUGUCUCCAGCUUUUCCAAUGGCUGCCCUGGAGAGGGCCCACGAUUCUCAGCUCCCCGGCGGCUCUCGACAAGCAGCCUGCGGCACCCCUCGCUUGGGGAAGAGUCCACCCAUGCCCUCAUUGCUCCUGAUGAGCAGUCCCACACCUAUGUCAACACACCGGCCAGUGAAGAUGACCACCGCAGGGGCCGCCACUGCCUGCAGCCCCUGCCUGAGGGUCAGGCACCCUUCCUCCCGCAGGCCCGGGGACCUGACCAACGGGACCCACAGGUGUUCUUGCAGCCAGGCCAGGUGAAGUUUGUGUUGGGCCCGACCCCUGCUCGGCGGCACAUGGUGAAGUGCCAGGGCCUCUGUCCCAGCCUGCAUGACCCCCCACACCACAAUAAUAACAAUGAGGCCCCUUCUGAGUGUCCAGCCCAGCCCAAGUGCACCUACGAGAACGUCACCGGGGGGCUGUGGCGAGGGGCUGGCUGGAGACUGAGCCCAGAGGAGCCGGGCUGGAAUGGCCUUGCCCACCGCCGGGCCGCCCUGCUGCACUAUGAGAACCUGCCCCCACUGCCCCCUGUGUGGGAAAGCCAAGCCCAGCAGCUGGGAGGGGAGGCUGGGGAUGAUGGGGACUCGAGGGAUGGGCUCACACCCUCUUCCAAUGGCUUCCCUGAUGGUGAGGAGGACGAGACCCCACUGCAGAAGCCCACCAGCACCCGGGCCGCCAUCCGCAGCCACGGCAGCUUUCCUGUGCCACUGACCCGCCGCCGCGGCUCCCCAAGGGUCUUCAACUUUGAUUUCCGCCGGCCGGGGCCCGAGCCCCCAAGGCAGCUUAACUACAUCCAGGUGGAGCUAAAGGGCUGGGGUGGAGACCGCCCUAAGGGGCCCCAGAACCCCUCGAGCCCCCAAGCCCCCAUGCCCACCACCCACCCUGCCCGAAGCUCAGACUCCUACGCCGUGAUUGACCUCAAAAAGACCGUGGCCAUGUCCAACCUGCAGAGAGCUCUGCCCCGAGACGAUGGCACCGCCAGGAAAACCCGGCACAACAGCACCGACCUGCCUCUGUAGGGACUUCCCGGUCCUCACCACCCUCUGCCCCACCAUGAUCCAGCCUCUGCCUCACACUCCUGUCCUCUGAACCCACCCUCCCCAGGGUUCAGGGUUGCUUUGCAGAAGGCAUGGAGGUGGGACCAGAUGCUUCCCUGUGCUGGCUGGAGUCCCCAGAGAUAUCAGCCACCGAGUCUCCUGGUCUGUCUCCAGGCUGGGGAGAGAAGGGUGACCAGGCGAGGAGGGAGCCGAGACGUCAACUGUGAAGGGUUCCUGUGAUUGCGUUUAGCGCCCUCCCGUUCUGUCCAUUUGUCUUGUCUGCCGACUGUCCGUGUGUGUUUUUUUUGGUUGGAAUUUUGAAACAUUUUGUACCUGUUGAUUUUAUUUAUCAGUUUAUUUUUCUAUUUAUUGUUUUAAAUGUAAUUUAACAUAUUUAUUAUUAAUAUAAUUAUUUUUAAAUUCUG